UGACUGCAUCACCUGGUCUGUGAAUUUUCCAUUAGAAGCUUGGUGUGCUGUUAGGUGAAAGACUUGCUCAGCUAUGCGUCAUUGGGUUUUAUCAACAUAUAGGCGAAAAAAAUCCUGGUCUCUGAGUGUACAGCUGAGAUGAAAAUUUCUUUUAUUGGAGGAAGUAUUGAGUGUGUGCUCUCAAAUGCGGCCUCAGUUGAGUAGUGCAUUCCUGAGUUUUGGAAGCAAAUUUGCAAACAAUUGAGAGUCGUACAGUGGGUGUUCUAACUGGAUUCAGGUUUUUUCUAAUGUAAUUUUUUCACACGUAAAUUAAAAAGUUUAGAAAUGUCACACAUAACUUCAUAACACUUUAUGGAGAAAUGGUUGUACUUUUAAUUUUUUUCUUUUUAUUUAUACUCCAACUGACUGAGCAGAGGUUGUACUUCUAAAUAACUUUGUGGAAGUUUUUAGUACCAUAAUUUUUAUAAUUUUCAUUCCAGUCCUUUGAUAUUUAUGACAGUACUUCUGAAGCGCUUACUGAGUGCCGGACACUGUUGUAAGUGCUUUACGGAACUUGACUUUUUUUUUUUUUUGAGACGGACUCUCGCUCUGUCGCCCAGGCUGGAGUGCAGUGGUGCAGUGGCUCGAUCUCGGCUCACUGCCACCUCUCCCUCAUGGUUUCAAACACUUCUCCUGCCUCAGCCUCCCAGGUAGCCAGGAUUAUAGCCGCCCGCCACCACUCCCGACUAAUUUUAUUUUGUAUGUUCUUUUUUAGUAGAGACGGAGGAGUUUCACCAUGUUGGCCAGGCUGGUAUCGACCUCCUGACCUCAAGUGAUGUGUCCAUCUCGGCCUCCCAAGGUGCUGGAAUUACAGGUGUGAGCCACUGUGCUCGGCCUACCUUUUUUUUUUUGUUUUUUGUUUUUUUGAAAAGGAGUUUCGCUCUUGUCCAGGCUGGAGUAUAAUGGUGCGAUCUCAGCUCACCGCAAUCUCCGCCUCCCAGAUUCAAGCGAUUCUCCUGCCUCAGCCUCCUCAGGAGCUGGGAUUACAGGCGCCCACCGCCAUGCCCGGCUAAUUUUUGUAUUUUUAGUAGAGACGGGGUUUCACUAUAUUGGCCAGGCUGGUCUCGAACUGCUGACCUCAAGUAAUCCGCCUGCCUCAGCCUCCCAAAGUGCUGGGAUUACAGACGUGAUCCACCAGGAUCACACCAGGCCGCGCCUGGCCUGCUUUCAUUUUAAAAGUCAAAUUUGUCAUCCGCCUCAGUGCUUGUAAUCUUUUCUGAGUGAGAUACUGAAAUUUGCAGUUUCGUUUUGCUUGCACUUGUUCACUGGACCAGUAGUCACUGUUAAAUGUAAAAGUAUCUACUUCCUCUGAAAGUUUUUUAUUCCUUUAUUUCCUGCCUGGGCUUGUCCUCCACCCUACAUGUAUGCGUAGUAGAUUUAGUGUUUGUUAUCCUAACCUUUAGGUUUAGGGAUUGACUGGGUUUCUGACUUUUUAUUUGGCCAAUGAGGACGAUACAGAAAAUGAAGCAUUGGUCAUUAUCACAUUUUAACGCUGAAAAAGUAAGAAGGACAACCCCGGAAUAAAAUGAUAUCAGUAUCAAGAUAAAAGUUUGGAAUGGGAGAAAAAUUCUCAAAGCCUGAAAGAAAAUCUGUAGUUACUUUUGGUGACGCUGUCCAGUUCCCACAAUGUAUCAUUCCUUAUCUGAAACUAGACAUCCUCUGCAGCCAGAAGAACAAGAAGUAGGCAUUGACCCCUUGUCCAGUUACUCUAACAAGUCUGGAGGAGAUUCAAAUAAAAAUGGAAGAAGAACAAGUUCUACUUUAGACUCUGAAGGGACUUUUAAUUCCUAUAGGAAAGAAUGGGAAGAACUAUUUGUAAACAACAAUUACUUGGCAACAAUAAGGCAGAAGGGGAUUAAUGGGCAGCUGAGAAGCAGCAGGUUCCGCAGCAUUUGCUGGAAGCUAUUUCUUUGUGUUCUUCCUCAAGACAAAAGUCAAUGGAUAAGUAGAAUUGAAGAAUUAAGAGCAUGGUAUAGCAACAUUAAAGAAAUACAUAUUACCAACCCGAGGAAGGUUGUUGGCCAACAAGAUUUGAUGAUCAAUAAUCCUCUUUCACAGGAUGAAGGGAGUCUUUGGAACAAAUUCUUCCAAGAUAAAGAACUUCGAUCAAUGAUUGAACAAGAUGUCAAAAGAACGUUUCCUGAAAUGCAGUUUUUCCAGCAAGAAAAUGUGAGAAAAAUUCUUACAGAUGUUCUUUUCUGUUAUGCCAGAGAAAACGAGCAGUUGCUUUAUAAACAGGGCAUGCACGAACUGUUAGCACCUAUAGUCUUUGUCCUUCACUGUGACCACCAAGCUUUUCUACAUGCCAGUGAGUCUGCACAGCCCAGUGAGGAAAUGAAAACUGUCUUGAACCCUGAGUAUCUGGAACAUGAUGCCUAUGCAGUGUUCUCACAACUUAUGGAAACUGCUGAACCUUGGUUUUCAACUUUUGAGCAUGAUGGUCAGAAGGGGAAAGAAACACUGAUGACUCCCAUUCCCUUUGCUAGACCACAAGAUUUAGGGCCAACAAUUGCUAUUGUUACUAAAGUCAACCAGAUCCAGGAUCAUCUACUGAAGAAGCAUGAUAUUGAGCUUUACAUGCACUUGAACAGACUAGAAAUUGCACCACAGAUAUAUGGGUUAAGGUGGGUGCGGCUGCUAUUUGGACGAGAGUUCCCCCUGCAGGACCUUCUGGUGGUCUGGGAUGCCUUGUUUGCAGACGGCCUCAGCCUGGGUUUAGUAGAUUAUAUCUUCGUAGCCAUGUUACUUUACAUCCGAGAUGCUUUGAUCUCUAGUAACUACCAGACCUGUCUCGGCCUUCUGAUGCAUUACCCAUUCAUCGGGGAUGUACACUCACUGAUUCUUAAGGCUCUGUUCCUUAGAGAUCCAAAGAGAAAUCCAAGACCAGUGACUUAUCAAUUCCAUCCAAAUUUAGAUUAUUACAAAGCACGAGGAGCAGACCUCAUGAAUAAAAGCCGGACCAAUGCCAAAGGUGCUCCCCUGAAUAUAAAUAAGGUCUCUAAUAGCCUGAUUAAUUUUGGAAGAAAGUUGAUUUCCCCAGCAAUGGCUCCAGGCAGUGCAGGUGGCCCUGUACCUGGAGGCAACAGCAGUAGCUCCUCCUCUGUUGUAAUUCCUACCAGGACCUCAGCAGAGGCCCCAAGCCAUCACUUGCAACAGCAACAGCAGCAGCAGAGGCUGAUGAAAUCAGAAAGCAUGCCUGUGCAAUUGAACAAAGGGCUAAGUUCUAAAAACAUCAGUUCAUCUCCAAGCGUUGAGAGUUUGCCUGGAGGAAGAGAAUUCACUGGCUCUCCACCUUCAUCUGCUACUAAAAAAGAUUCCUUUUUUAGCAACAUCUCACGUUCUCGCUCACACAGCAAAACUAUGGGCAGAAAAGAAUCUGAAGAAGAAUUAGAAGCCCAAAUUUCCUUCCUUCAAGGGCAGUUGAAUGACCUGGAUGCCAUGUGCAAAUACUGUGCAAAGGUGAUGGACACUCAUCUUGUAAAUAUUCAAGAUGUGAUAUUACAAGAAAAUUUGGAAAAAGAAGAUCAAAUUCUGGUUUCCCUGGCAGGAUUAAAACAGAUCAAAGACAUUCUAAAAGGUUCCCUGCGUUUUAACCAGAGCCAGCUAGAGGCCGAAGAGAACGAACAGAUCACCAUUGCGGACAACCACUACUGCUCCAGCGGCCAGGGCCAGGGCCGAGGCCAAGGCCAGAGCGUUCAAAUGUCAGGGGCCAUUAAACAGGCCUCUUCAGAAACGCCAGGGUGCACUGAUAGAGGGAAUUCCGAUGACUUCAUCCUGAUUUCCAAAGAUGAUGAUGGGAGCAGUGCCAGGGGCUCCUUCUCCGGCCAGGCCCAGCCUCUUCGCACCCUCAGAAGCACCUCUGGGAAAAGCCAGGCCCCAGUCUGCUCCCCACUGGUGUUCUCAGAUCCACUGAUGGGCCCAGCCUCAGCUUCCUCCAGCAACCCCAGCUCCAGUCCUGAUGACGACAGCAGCAAGGACUCUGGCUUCACCAUUGUGAGUCCCCUGGACAUCUGACCACAGUGCCCAGUCCUGCCCCACAGGGAUCUAGCCACCCUUCAGUGGCCCCAAGGCCAGACUGAGGCUCAUCCAGUGGAGAACCUUCUUAAACCACUGCUUCCUUCCCGGCAUGCAUUUUGCAUUGGUCCAGCCCUUUGAAACCCCUUAGAGAGAAGCAUAUAUGGCCACAAAGCACAGAGGCUUAGGUUUGCCACAUGCAGACAGGGCUUUCUGGGCCCUUACCUAAUCCCCACCCGACUCUUGCUCUGAGUUAGAGCUGAGUUACGUACCCAGUAUCACACUCACAGUUAGAAAAGACCGAAUCACAAUUUAGAAUCACUUUUCCUCUGUCCCCUUCUCCCCAGCUAAGAAUGUGUGGCACCUCCAUCAGUUAUACUUAGAAGGAGCAGAAAUAGUUAUUUUCGUAUCUUCUAUCCCUCAAAGCAUCAGACAUGGGAAAAUUGGUUUAUACCAAGAAAGCUUCCUCUGUGGAAAUCUGUCUCAGCCUACUUUAUUCCUGCAUUGGGAAGCCAUAUCGCAGAGCUAAAUGCAAUAGAAUGAACCAGAACUAGUGGAUUCCAGGGCUGGGGGAAAAAAAAAAAGAAAAAACCUCAUUACUGACCUCUCAAAGUUAUAAGGAUCUCUGCAAACAGGAUCUAAGCUUAGGAAUAAUAUUUAGGUGUGAUAUAGUGUUAGAUUUUUUUGAUGUAUUAAAGAAUGCAUCUCCAAUCCUUAGGCCAUAUCAACUUUGGCCAUCAAUAUCUCUCCUUAAACAAUUAUAUUUCACCUUUUAGAAUCUUUCAUAGCCAGAAAACAAGAUUACUGUAAGCCAGUUUUAGCUGCACUGAUUUCAAAAGAUAUAAGAAUAUUACUAUCCUUCAAAUGGAAAAUGCGACCUUGACUUUAUGGGAUAAACAUCUUUCAGACAGUCAGUUUUCUAGUCAGGUUUCUCUGGUUUCAGAGCUGUAUAUACCUGUCAACUGAGGAAUAAAGGGAAAAACCCAAGUUCAUUCCCACCCAAAGUCAGAAUCCCUCAUUGGCCUUAAGGUAGCAGUCAUAAGACAGAGAAUUGGACCUAGAGUCCCUUCUGUGGGGAAUAAGGAUACCUAGAGAACAUUCCACAUGCCAAGAGGAUGCAGGAUUUCUACACAACCCCUUCCCUUCUUGGAAGUCAAGUGUAGGUACUGCAGGGCCUGUGCUCAGCUGUGAACCCCGUAUCCUGGGCCCCACUGCCGGGACCGGGUCUGACAUGCCAGUGCCUUCCUGGGCUGAGCACAGAUUAGAGACUCUCCCCCUUGUCAGUCAGCACCUUAGGAAACCAUGAUGGGCACAGAGCAUCACAUGAGCUGUUUCUCUCCUUAAAGAAGAUCCCUGGAAAGGAUGCUUUUCCUCUCCUUUGCCUGCGCAGGAAUUCUAACAGGAGUGGGUGAGGAUGGCAGAGGGACACAGUGCCUGUCUCGCCUCCAUCAGGGAGAGCAGCCAUGCCAGGGAUGACUAGCUCUUUGAGCCUGUCCUCAGAGGAUGGCGAGGCAGCCGGGCAGUGGAGGCCUUCAUGGUAACAAAUGAAAGCUCAGUAUAGAGGAACAGACACUGUUUACGUCCCUCCCACUGCUAACCUUAUAUAUCUCUAUAGACAAAUGUGAUAAUGACAUGAUUUCCCACCUGCCCUCCAAGAAAAUGGUGACUCACUCUCAAGUCAGCUACUGUAGAGAGGGUUCUAAUUGGUUCUGCAAUUUGCUCUUAAACUCUAGCAGGGAACUCUCCUCUUACCACAUCAGCAUGUAAGGUGAAUAAUAACUGGUUUUGCCAGACAGCAGGUUGUCUGACCUUCAACCACUGGGCAAUUGCCUGGCAGAUGCACACAGUAGCUCCCUGGCUUCUGGCUCUGAGUGUUCCUCUCAGCACCUCUGAGUAAGCUGCUGCCAAGCACAUAUCCCUAUGACAACACUUUGUAAAAGCCGCGGGGCCCCCAUACAGCGAGUGACCUUGCAACUGUGCAGGGUUGCCAUUGGUCACUUUCUCACCUUGGGAAGGUGUCAGUGUUUUCAGUUCUAAGGUAAGAGGUGUAGAGCUGUUCCCACCAGGGCUCUGGGACAGACUGGAAAGGACCACAGACCUGGCCAUCCCUGGGCAGCAGGGCCAGUGUCACCUGCUGACCUCUAGUAUUUCCUUUGCCCUAGAGCUAGAGUCAUGAUAGCUGAGGGUCACUCGCCCUGCAAGAGUCACUAGGCACCCACCAUGCCAAUAAGGCUCUCCGCUGGCUCCCUGCAGUUGGCUGGGUGUUUAAUAGUCACUGAAAACUCCCAGCCCUGCUGCACACUAGAGGCAGGUCCUCUCGGUCCUCUCCAUCCUGUGCUUCUGUGGCCCCCAGCAAGCUCACCACCUCCUUGGAGGAGAGAGACAUACAAGGACAGUGGGUCAUGGGUAGUACCAGCCUCAAAUUCCCACAGGCUCAUACUCAGACAAUUGUAUUACUGCCUUAUGUUUUUUAAGUGUUUUUUUAAAUUCUUCAUAGUUGAGUAUUAUUUGCAAUUUUAUUAGUUACAGUGCUAUUAAAGAAUAUGUGCUCCUUUUUAUUAUAUUAUCAGAUACUUAUGUUUAAUUGUACAUUUUUUAAAUCCUGAAUAUAUUGUGUUUUGUUAACAAAUGUAAUCAGUGGAACCCUUCUUACGUUUUGAUUAUUAGCAGUUAAAUACAUUUUGUAUACAUGAAGCUUAGAUUAAUUCCCAUCAUCAUCAUCUCCUGUUUUUAUAUGUGUCCCUAUGUGUUUCAUGCAUUCCUCUUUGAUCAGAUUGGAAUUUGAGUUAAAAUUUAGCUUUGUACAUUACGUGUGAGAGUUACAGACUAGCAAGUCUAAUUACUUUGCCUUACCUUGAGUGUAUGCCACAGGGUCAGAUAACACAUUAAACAUUUAGUUACACUGGAUUACUCUUCCAAAGCUGACCUCCUGCUAAUGUUCAGAGGUAACUGCAAUCCGGAAAGAAAUAAUAUCACUGCAGAAAGAAUGUGACUCUAAAAAUAAACCAGGACCUCCCUGUGAUUUGCCUUGCCUGCAGAUGACCAGUUGACUCUUGUGCUGUCAGCCCUGGGGUUGCUAAGGAAGCUGCUUCAGGGAGUUGGGGGUUAGUUGCCCGCUCUCAACAGGAAUGCCUCCUCUACUUUGUCAGAGAUGCUGAACAAAUAUCAAACUCUGUGGCAGUCAUGCUGGCCUCCUAAGAAUAACCUGUGAGUCAGAGUUGAUGCACAUUAUUUUUGUUUUUAUUUUAUUUUUUUAAGGAACUGCUCCAAGGGUUCAUUAUAGAACAGGAGUGUGUACGGAGGACUUAGGUCCCCACAUAGAGUGGCCGUUCUGUGGCGGCUCCAACCAAUUCCAUCCCUCCUUUCCUGCGGACACACACCUGGCCCCUGGCCCCUGCCCUGUGUGUCUGGAGGAGGGGCACUGGGGAGGCUGUGGAGCAGAGAGAAGAGGCCGGAUACAUUGAGGAUGGCACCUGGCAAGCCAGGCUUCCUUCUCAAAGGCCAGACUGCUUUCUCAGUGUUACUUACUAAAGCUCUCUUUUUAUACUGUUAAAAAGAUAUAUAAAGUUCGUAUAAACAGGCUUGAGACCACUUUGAUGUAAAAGCUGUCAUAGUAGUUUUUCUCACAGUGGCACAAUUCAUUUGAUUGAUGGAAUAUUCAGUGACGCCAUGUAUGCCCUAUCGCUUUUUUCUCAUCCAUCUUUAUGCUAUAACUCAUACUGAUUUAAGAAAUGAUUUCUCCUUUUGGCAAAGCGACCCCAUUCAAUAUGGUUAUAAUAAAAGACUAAUGUCAAACUGAGA